GGAAUAUCUAUAAAGGAAUUCGGGCCCCUACGUGAGAAGCUCGGAGGGGGUGGUUUCAGGAGUUCCUUGUGGAGAGGGGAUCGUCCGUGACUCAGACCCCGUCGAAAAGCUCUCGAUUUCACGCAACCAACCUUACCCUCGUCCCCAACACAAUCCUUGAUUUUACCCCUGGGAAAAUUAGCGUAGGUGGUCAUGACCCCGGCUUCCUCUUUAAAAGCCCUCAGAACCUGGACCGGGCUCCUCAAUGAACCCUAGUGUUAGAGGCCACAAAUCGGGAACCAAGGUCGGGGAGCGGCUGUUUAGGGUGCAUCACUGUUCAGGAUGCAUCGGGGCUCCUUUUUCUAAGCGGAAGGGUGCGCCCUGCAAAUUGGGAGCCCGUUAGUUUUGGGGAAGGGUGAACAAGGGCCCCCUAGGUCUAGAGGACCGCAUGGAGUCUCGCUUAAGUGUUAGUGGGGUCCUCAGUUCUAGGAAUCUGCGUUCUCCUGCUCUCGGUUUGGGGUGAGAGCACCCUUCCUAACGGUCUUCGGGAACUGUGCGCGCCGGCUGCAAUGGGGCCGCAUUUUACCCUCCUGUGUGCGGCGCUGGCCGGUUGCUUGCUUCCUGCCGAGGGGUGUGUUAUAUGUGACCCGUCUGUCGUGCUGGCGCUAAAGUCCCUGGAGAAAGAUUACCUGCCUGGCCACCUGGAUGCGAAGCAUCACAAAGCCAUGAUGGAAAGGGUAGAGAAUGCCGUGAAGGAUUUCCAGGAACUGUCGCUUAAUGAGGAUGCCUAUAUGGGGGUCGUUGAUGAGGCCACACUGCAAAAGGGGUCCUGGAGUUUGCUGAAGGAUCUGAAACGCAUCACAGACAGUGAUGUAAAAGGCGAUCUCUUCGUGAAGGAGCUAUUUUGGAUGUUGCACUUGCAAAAGGAAACCUUUGCCACCUAUGUUGCUCGAUUCCAAAAAGAGGCUUAUUGUCCCAACAAAUGUGGUGUGAUGUUGCAAACUCUGAUCUGGUGCAAGAACUGCAAAAAGGAGGUUCACGCUUGUCGAAAGUCCUACGAUUGCGGGGAGCGGAAUGUGGAAGUUCCUCAAAUGGAAGACAUGAUCCUGGACUGUGAGUUAAACUGGCAUCAGGCUUCGGAAGGCCUCACUGAUUACAGCUUUUACAGGGUUUGGGGGAACAAUACGGAGACCUUGGUGUCCAAGGGGAAAGAGGCCACCCUGACCAAGCCCAUGGUGGGUCCAGAGGAUGCAGGCAGCUACCGCUGCGAGCUGGGCUCUGUGAAUUCCAGCCCAGCCACGAUCAUCAAUUUUCACGUCACAGUGUUGCCCAAAAUGAUCAAGGAGGAAAAACCUUCUCCAAAUAUCGUAACCCCGGGGGAGGCGACCACGGAGUCGUCCAUAAGCCUCCAGCCUCUGCAGCCCGAGAAAAUGCUGGCAAGCCGCCUUCUGGGGCUGCUGAUCUGCGGCUCCCUAGCACUGAUAACCGGCCUUACCUUUGCGAUAUUUCGUCGAAGGAAGGUGAUCGAUUUCAUCAAAUCCUCACUGUUUGGCCUUGGCAGUGGAGCGGCCGAGCAAACCCAGGUCCCAAAAGAAAAGGCCACAGAUUCGAGGCAACAAUAAAGAUUUAUCUUGUUGUCUAAGCAUCUGACUCACUCCCCGGGACGGGACUGAUUCUA